AGUUUCUUUUCACUUAUUAGUCUACUAGGAUACUUGAAUACUGUCUCUAUGCUGGUGUCUAAAACCCUCAAAGGAGAGUACAAUUGCAGGAUAAACGAAGAGUGUCCAGGAAGAGAACUAGACAAGAAAGGAAACAGAUGGUCUCUGGGCUCGGUGAGCUUGGAAGCUGUCGAAAGCAAACUCGACUGGACCCUCCAAACUCCUAUUUCAGAUCAAUACAUAAGGUUCAGCUGAGUUCGGCCUCCAGGCCCAAGAAAGCAAAAGCCAGCAACCCGGGGGCUGGUCGGCGGCUCCCUCGCCAGGGACGCCCCACAGCGAGACCAUGCCUCUCCCACCUCUACCCCCGAAAACCAAAACAAAACAGAACCAAGCCCAAGCGGUGCUUGCUCGUUUCUUUUGUCUUGCUCAACGCUGACCACUUUUUUUCCGGAGAAGGUUAACGUUAAGGGAGCCCGGGGGAGCUCUCUGCGACCCCGCCAGGUGCUCCCCGAACCCCCGGCCCCAUCAGAGGAAUGAGGCGACCACCGAGCGGCGUUGGGCGGCCAGGUCCUCCCCGGCACCCCCGCCCCGGCUCCUGGAGGAGGGCAGGGACUGCCGGCCUGGGGCAGCCAGGGACCGACGGGACCCCCGCAGAGCCAGGCCCGAGGCCCCGGGCGCCCCCACGACCCGGCGGCCGCCCAGGGCGCCCGCCUGGGGCCUCACCCCAACCGGGGACAGGGCCGCCGAGGGCCGGGCCAAGGCCGCCCGGCUUGUCCCCGAGGCCGCCGGGGAGCGUAGGCCGCCGCCAUCCCCGGCCUGCCGUGCGCCCGCAGCCCGCGGCCUUACCGCCUCCACGGCGUGCUGCAGGAUGGAGGUGAACUUGGAGAACAUCCUGUCCCGGGACUGCAGCAGCCUCUCCCGGGACGACCUGGAGAGCUCCUCGAUCCGCCGCCGCCGCCCCUGCUGCGGCUGCCGGGGCCGCUCCAGAGUGAAGGCCGGUGCGGGGCGGGGAGGACGAGCUGAGGAUCGAGGCAGGGCCUGGCCCGGCCGCUUCAGGUGUGCGCGGGCGGCUCGGCGGCUCCGGAGGGCGCCGGGACGCGGCGGGCGGCGAGGAGGGCGUUCGGCGAGGACUCGGGGCCCGGAGAAGCUCCGGCGGCGGCACCGGUUGGGACACGGUGGCAGCCCGGCUCGGGUUCCUUCCCCCCGCUCUGCCCGCCGCGGCCUGCAGGGGGCGCCGCCGCAGCCCGGGGAGGCCCGGCCAGGCCUGCCCUGCGGCGGGGCCGCUAGGCGCCGCGGGGGCGGGGGGCGCGCUGAGGCCUCGGCCUCGCGCGGGGCUGGAGGCGGCCUGUGGGCAGCCACCGCCCUCUCCCGGCUUUCUCAGGGCGCCUGGGACACCGGCUUUCUAACAUUUUUACAGCUCAGCGAUUCUCAAGAGUUUUGUUUCUCCAGUGGAAGUAACAGGCUGACUUUGUAGGGACACGCAGCCGUCCAUAUAUGCGUAUAGCAUUCAGAGGUUCUUCCUGUAAGGACCGAUUUGGAAGACUCGUUAAGAAAACAGUGUUCUUUAAGCAAACAUUGGCAAUGGAUUUAAAUGCUCAGAUUUUGAAGAAAUCAACGACUGCAGGUGAAAUGGCUUUGCUAACUUUAAAAUAUAUUAUUAUUCAACAUUGAAACAGGAAAUCCCACAUGAGCACAUGGUAAGACGGCUGGCUUAGUUUAAAUAGCCCAUUAUAAUAUUUAUAUAUAAUAUAUAACAUAAUUUAUUUGUGAUAUGGUUGAUAGUGAGGUGUAGUGAUUCAGAACAGCAUUUUCUAUUCAGUUAUCAGAUGAUACCGGAAAACAUUAGCGAGGGAAAGAAUCUGAAAGGAGUCCAGUAAAUGCCUAAGGCAGAUAAAUAGAGCUACAAGAUAAAUACGACCUUAAUUUUCUACGUACUACCCCCAGAAUGCUGGAGGCAUCCUCUGUUGUUUUGUGCCCCUUACCAAAUUCUGGCCGUGUCUGCUUCAACUGAGAGCAUGUAUGUAUGCUUAUUGUUAUUAUAUUCAUACACAGUUUAAGAUGGUUAGUCAUAUUAUUAACCAUAAUUAGUUUCAUGAUCUAAUUAUCAUGCAUUUAUAUGGCAUUUUGUAGUUCCAAAAUGCCUUACAACCACUAAUUGUAUGAGGAGGUCUUAGUUAGAGUUGUGUGUAUUUGAUGAUGUCUAUCUUUGUGUACUUAUUAUAAACACAAUAAAAUAUAUGUUUUGCUCUAGAUUAAUAUCAAUAUUUAGGAUGGUGAUUCAUCUACCUGCUGUCUAGGUUUCAAGACACACAAGUUGGACUAGAAUUGUAACUGAGCAGAUAUUCCUAUUUCUGAUUGUCAUCCUAGAAUGCCUGCUGUGACUCUGACAUCAUCAAUUAGCUCAAUACAUGGGCACAGUCGGACCUGCCCCAAAGCCUGUGAUUUGAGAAAACACAAGAAAACCUUCCCCUAGCCUCCAAACCACUUAGGUGUGGGUACCUGAAAUUUCUCAGUUAGAACUUAAUGCCUUUAUCCCUUUGGCUUAAGCCAAAUAAGAAACUUAGUCCUUGUUAAAAUGAAAAUACUCUUGGGAGAUGUAACACAUCAAACUCUGUCAUUCAUUAGACUUCAGGGGGAAUGAAUUUGUUAAAUCCUUUUCUAAAAUGAAGUUUAAUUAGUGAAGACACAGAAAAAUCUAGAAAAUUGGAACCCAGUUGGGAUGGUGUUGAGAAAAGAGAUAAAAAUAAAUCUUUUUUUAACUUUUUAAUAAUAGUCAUUCUGACUGGUGUGAGAUGAUAUCUCAUUGUGGUUUUUAUUUGCAUUUCUCUAAUCAGUGAUAUUGAGCUUUUUUUCAUAUGCUUGUUGGCCACAUAUAUGUUUUCUUUUAAAAAAUGUCUGUUCAUGUCCUUUGUGCACUUUUUAAUGGGGUUGUUUGUGUUUUUUUCUUAUAAAUGUGUUUAAAUUCCUUAUAGAUCCUGGGAUAUUAGACCUUUGUUAGAUGCAUAGUUUGCAAAUAUUUUCUCCCAUUCUGUAGGUUGUCUGUUUACUCUGUACAAUAAACACCGAUGACAUGAGUUUUACCUAUAUAACAAA